CACUCUCCCCACCUUACAUCCCUCACCUCAGUCCUUCACCCCCUUAACCUAAUCUCCAUGUCCUCACACCAUACACUCCUGAUCCUGAAGUCUGCACACCCUGGGCUUCUCAUUCCGUGCAGCCUGCCCCUCUUACCCUCACACCUGCCACACCUGGGACCCCGGAGUCCACACACCACCUCACACCCCAAGUUCCCACACGCACCUCUGGCUUCCUCCACCUGCACUUCAGGACCCGCCCAGACUCUUCAUAGCCCAACUCCAAGACUUCUCUCCCACAUCACAGAUGGAUGAUGCUGACCCUGAGGAAAGAAACUAUGACAACAUGCUGAAAAUGCUGUCAGAUCUGAAUAAGGACUUGGAAAAGCUAUUAGAAGAGAUGGAGAAAAUCUCAGUGCAGGCGACCUGGAUGGCCUAUGACAUGGUGGUGAUGCGCACCAACCCUACGCUGGCCGAGUCCAUGCGUCGGCUGGAGGAUGCCUUCGUCAACUGCAAGGAGGAGAUGGAGAAGAACUGGCAAGAGCUGCUGCAUGAGACCAAGCAAAGGCUGUAGGCCCCACUGGCCCACCACAGCUGCCAUGCCACCCUCUGCCCGUAUGAAGAGGUCACUGGGGGAUGGAGCUGGCACCCACAUGAAUAGCUGUAUGCACUGUACUUGUUUCUUAAUAAACUUAUUUUUAAGCACA